AUCGCUUGUCCUGAGCUGGUUGCCGGGGCAGGGGCGGAGGCGGAGGCAGAGGUGGAGGCGCUUUGAAAGGUGAGAGCGCGAGGGCGGUGCGGGGCUGUCUCCCGGCUGGGACUCGCUCGCGCUCCCGGUGCUAAUGGUUUAUGAGAGGGGCGGGGGAAGCCGUGCCUCCUCGCGGACUAAGAGAAAAAUUCCCGCGGGCGCUCUUUGGGUGGGCCGGAGAACGCCCCUCAGCCCUUUGCGCCUCUAACCCUCCUCAGCUGAGCUGCAGUGGGCGCGGUGCCCGUUAUUUCCGCCUUGGGGAGGUGCUUGGAACUGAUGUAGGGAGCUCGGUUGGUGAUUUCUCGGGUUUCUGGCCUUUCCAGACCCUUGUAAUUGUUUUCUCGGUGCAGAGCUCUUUUGGGGUCUGGGGGUUUCCGUCGUCCUGCGCGCGUCAUCGCGAAGCUUGGCCUGAGGGUCCGGUUUCCUAGCUACUGUGCCCCUCCCUCCUGGAGGCAGAGUGACGGACUAGUGGGCUAGCGGGCGCUGGGUUCCUGCGUCCCGCCAAAGAGGUUUGUAAUCAUGAAAGUCACCCUUCCGGGUGUUAAUUCCUGAGAGGAUCUAUUCCACUGUCUACCACUCAUUCCUGCUGCAUUAACCUUCAUUGUUAACGGAUUUUAAUGAAUAAUAUAGUUAUCCCGGAUACCAUGCUGGCAGGAUCCACUUUGCGAAAUUGUGGACUGUUGGACUGUGAUUCUAAGUGGGGGAAAUAGGCUUUCCUCUCUUUAUGUUUAUUUUCUUAUAUCCUAUUUCUGUCAUGUUCUGUCUUGUUUUCCUGCCAAUAGAAGAACUAUGAUAAAUUUAUUCAUAGCAGUGUGAUAAGAACUUGAUCUUAAUCAUACACUGUAGCCCUCAAAUCGUGUAUUAUGCUGGCUUGUUUUUGGUGUCCCUAGUAAUUUCAUCAGAUUGUGAGCUCCUUGGGAGCAGAGACCAUGUUUAUUUGAAAUGGUGGCAGCACAGUUCCUAGCAGGUGCUUGCAUUUUGGUAGAUAUUCAAUAAUUAUUUUUCGGCUUAUUAAUCUUUGCUCUCCAAACUGCCAUAUAAAAGAAAACAUCGAAGAGGAGUGAUGUUUUACACCCAAGAAUGGAUCCCUCCUGGUAGAAUUUCAAAUAAUGACCUGGGGUUCCACUGCCUUUCAAAUCUGUAAAGUGUUAACUACCACCUGCAUUGUUUAUACAGCAAGUAGGUGAUUUCUAGAAUGAAUCUUUUCUUGAGUAUGAAUUAACCUCAAAGUUUAGAAGGAACUAUAUUUCUUCUGAUGAGAAAGUCAAAUGGCAUCAUCAAAGUACUUUUAGCUAUAGAGUUACUGUGUUAGAGAAAGAACACAAGCAAUAUGGAUUAUUGUCUUUAAUAUAUAUUCUUUGGCAGAUAACAUAGCUAUGUAUGUGCAUCUUAUAUUAACCAUGAAACACAAAGAUGUGAUAGUAUUGAUCAUCUUCAUUCACUUAUUUAAUGCUUUCUGUUUGGAGUCUCUGUUUUUCUCUUUGCUUAAAGGUAAGGUAUCAUUACAGAAGCUCGAUAAAAUUCUCAUUUCAGGAAAUUAAGUGUAUAUUCAACAUAUACAGAAGUAACAUUCAUUUGCAUGGAUUCUCUUUUGAGUAGAUUCUGAAGACCAAGAGGUAUCUUACCCAUCAAACUAGCUUUCCUUCACAUUUCUCUUCCGAGGUUCACUCACCUUUUCCCUCCGUUAUCAUUCUUCCCUUCCCAGCUAAUAUAGUAAAGCUACCUACAAUUUAAAAAGAAGAGCCAAACAUAUUCAAAGUGUCUUUCCUUUUCAGUAACAGAAUUUUUUACCUUACUGAUAUAAAUGGUCAUUUUGAAAUAUGAGAGACCCUGGCAAUUUGGCAGUUGGUCCAAUGAAACCUGAUUUAUUUUGUUUAAAUAAAAGAUGCUGCCUCAGGCAUUCAAAUUCUGCAGUUUUCCAAAAUAUGUUUCUCAUCAGAGACUGCCUUUCUUUGAAAUUUUACUUUUGGGCUCACUGGGGACUCCUUUAAAUUUUGCAAUUGGUGUUAUUAAUAAGAUGAUAAGAGGGAAGUCUGCAAAUACUCUUUUCUUGCCUGGUGGAUAAUAAUUUACAGAAGUUUCUGGCCUAACUCGUGCAGUAAAAUUCGGUUACAUAAUUUUUUAAAAAAGCAUAUUUGUAAACUCUAAACCAUUUUAAUCGUUAUUUUUCUGAAACUAAAAUACAGCAUGAAUGAGAGAUAAAAAUAAUGAUUUUUAAAGGCUUAAUUUUUACUAUCUUGUACAAAUGUGAUAUUGGCAGCCGUCAUUGUGUGGCACUGGACGGGGAAUCAAGAGACCCGGUUUCUAAUCCCUGCUCUGUCACUAACAAGCUGCGUGAUCUUCGGUAAGUCAUUUAAACUCUAUGUCCUUGGCUUUGAUAUUUACACAUAAAAAUAGAUAUCUUCCUUCUAGGAUCAUUGUCAGGAUUUAAAAAUCAAUGUGAAAAUGCACUAAAAACUUAAAGUUUCUUUUAUGGCUUAACUGUGCAGUCAUAAGUUUUUAAUAGUGUGAUUCUUAAUCAUUUCCACCAUUGUCAUAGGAAUCACCUGUUUCAUGAUAAAUAACUGACAUUCUGGGCAUGUUAUAGUUUUGUAAGAUAAUCAUCUAGUGUAUAUGAAUUUGCUUUUGGGUACUAAUAAAAAUCAUCGUUAACUUUAAUGUUCUUUACUGUCCAUAUUUGCUUUAGUGUAUCUACUGCAACCAUAUUUGUCAUUGUUUUCAUAAAUGUUUUUUCAUUAUUUCUCCCAAUUCAAACAGGUUUAUUAGAAAGCCAUGCUUUGUUAUUACAAUGUGAUAUACUACACGUGCACAUAUGCACACUUAGCUUACGCAAAUUUAUGUGUUUACAAAUACUUUUUUGUACUAUACAGCUUAAAAAUGUAAGAUGCCUAGUUCGUGUGGUGCUAAACCAAAGAAACAGUAAGCUGCUUAAAACCUGGAGGAGAAACUGGGUGGACGUAUUGUAACGCAGUAUAGUGUACACAAAACCAUACUUUAAUAUAGAGAUUUUUUUAAAGGGUAAUUUUGACUACACACAAUUUUCAUCUUUGCUGAUUUUAAUAUAAGCCUUUUGUAAGAUGCAACCCAAGGGUAAUUUCAAAUAGCAGACUGCCCUGUUGACCAGAAUUUGUUAGAUUGCUAUUACAAUGCUGAUUAUAUUUUAUAGCAAUUACUGACAUAAGGUUAUACUUUGGGCAAUGGCUCAUGCCUGUAAUCCCAGCACUGAGGCCAAGGUGGGAGGAUCACUUGAGGUCAGGAGAUCAGGACAUAGUGAGACCUCCAUCUCUACAAAAAAUUUAAAAAUCGAAACAUAUCGCUUGAGCCCCAGGAGUUCAAGGCUGUAGUAAUCUAUGAUCAUGCCACUGCACUCCAGCCUGGACAACAGGACAAGACCUAUCUCUUAAAAAAAUAAAAGUUAUAUUUCAUCCUACACGCUAUAAUUUCUGCUGUAUAAUUUUGGCAGCCCCCGUUCUGAUUUUACAUGAGGUGUUAACCAUUAUACAGAAAGUCUUAUUGCCGUAUAAACAUACCAGAAUUUGUACAAUUAAAUGAGCUGUAUCCUCUCUUCCACAAUCUAUAGGAAAAAAGUAAUCCUCUUGGAAAGCUGGAAACAUAGUCCGAUUUUUUAUAGUGUGUGGUUUAUAGAAAGACUCCAGGAAUAUUCUGUGCUGUGGUGGAAAUAUUGGAAUAAUCAGCCUCAUAAGAAGCUUAAGUGAAAAUGAUACAUGUUAGAAGACAUGAAACAAGGAGAAAUUCUAAGAGUCACGUGCCUGAGCAGAAAUCUCGAGUUGAUUGGAGGCGAACUAAAAGAAGUAGUAUCUCACAAUUACUUGAUAGUGAUGAAGAGCUUGAUAGUGAAGAAUUUGAUAGUGAUGAAGAGCUUGAUAGUGAUGAAAGUUUUGAAAAUGAUGAAGAGCUUGAUAGUAACAAGGGACCUGAUUGUAAUAAAACACCAGGAAGUGAAAGAGAGCUCAACUUAAGUAAAAUUCAAAGUGAAGGAAAUGACAGUAAGUGUCUCAUUAACUCUGGCAACGGUUCAACAUAUGAAGAAGAAACGAACAAAAUCAAACAUAGGAAUAUUGACUUACAAGAUCAGGAAAAACAUUUAAGUCAAGAGGAUAAUGAUCUCAACAAACAAACUGGACAAAUAAUAGAGGAUGAUCAGGAAAAACAUUUAAGUCAAGAGGAUAAUGAUCUCAACAAACAAACUGGACAAAUAAUAGAGGAUGAUUUAGAAGAAGAAGACAUCAAGCGAGGAAAAAGAAAAAGGCUAUCCUCUGUGAUGUGUGACAGUGAUGAGAGUGAUGACAGCGAUAUCCUAGUUAGAAAAGUAGGUGUUAAACGUCCCCGUAGAGUGGUUGAAGAUGAAGGUUCUUCAGUGGAAAUGGAGCAAAAGACUCCUGAAAAAACAUUAGCUGCACAAAAGCGAGAAAAACUUCAGAAGCUCAAAGAACUCUCAAAACAAAGAUCUCGUCAGAGACGCAGUAGUGGUAGAGAUUUUGAGGACUCUGAAAAGGAAUCUUGCCCAAGCAGUGAUGAAGUUGAUGAGGAGGAAGAAGAGGAUAAUUAUGAAUCUGAUGAAGAUGGAGAUGAUUAUAUUAUCGAUGACUUUGUAGUGCAAGAUGAGGAGGGUGAUGAAGAGAAUAAAAACCAACAAGGAGAAAAAUUGACUACAUCACAACUGAAAUUAGUAAAACAGAAUUCUCUUUAUUCUUUUAGUGACCACUAUACUCAUUUUGAAAGAGUUGUGAAGGCUCUUCUGAUCAACGCUUUAGAUGAAUCUUUUCUGGGAACAUUAUAUGAUGGCACAAGGCAAAAAUCAUAUGCAAAAGAUAUGCUAACAUCUCUUCAUUAUUUGGAUAACCGCUUUGUUCAGCCUCGUCUAGAGAGCUUGGUAUCUAGAAGUCGUUGGAAAGAGCAAUAUAAGGAGCGAGUAGAAAAUUAUUCUAAUGUAAGUAUUCAUUUGAAGAAUCCUGAAAACUGUUCCUGCCAGGCUUGUGGACUGCAUCGCUACUGUAAAUAUUCAGUGCAUUUAUCAGGAGAGUUGUAUAACACCAGGACCAUGCAAAUAGAUAAUUUCAUGUCACAUGAUAAACAGGUGUUCACUGUUGGCAGAAUUUGUGCCAGCCGUACCAGAAUUUAUCAUAAACUGAAACAUUUUAAAUUCAAACUAUACCAGGAAUGUUGCACCAUUGCAAUGACAGAAGAAGUUGAAGAUGAACAAGUUAAAGAAACAGUGGAAAGAAUUUUCAGGCGGUCAAAAGAAAAUGGCUGGAUUAAGGAGAACAGUUCUUGUGACCUGAGAGUGAAGAAGCACCUGGUGCCAGUCUGAGGAAAGGAUCUCGGCUGCCAGUUCUAAUACACCCACAUCCUCUUCUUGAGGACAUGGGACUGAGCAGUGAGCACUGUAACUGAAGAUCGAGGGGAAUGCAGAGGUUUCAGACCACAGCACUGAUUUUGAUUCCCCCAUAUCCUAUUGAUCACUAAAUUUGAUAACAGGAGUAAAGUGGGGGUUUUGAAGAGUGCACUGGAUUCCCGAAGAUCUGCUGGCAGCUUACAAGCUCUGGUCUGCUCACAGAGCUUUUAGAAUUGUUUAUGGUAUAUGGAAAGAAUGCUAAUACGACUGCAGUCUUCUAAAACAAGUCUAGUUACAUGAAUGUAUAAGAGAGAACAAAUAGUAGAUUUUCAGGCAACUCUUAUCAACAUUUAAUCUUUUAAAGAAAAGAAAAAAGCCUAACUUGAGAUCCAUUGCCUGGACUAUAUCAUAGGGAAAUUUGUAAAAGAGGAAUAUAAAAAAUAAGGCAAGAGAGCUUAGGCAGAUGGAAAGAAAACAAAACAGAAACUUUUUUAGCACAUGUCAUAUUUAGUGGAGGUCUCCCAGUCUAGAUAAUGACAUCAUCACUGGUUUCCCUUUGACAAUUUUUCUCCCACCACAAACCACCACCCAGUGAUCUUGCCUGCCCCCCACAUCUUGAUCCUUAAGUCUUUCUCUCAUUUUAUUCUUUUCAGCUUUUUGUCUUUUACUUUGCUUCUACUUCUCCUACUCCAAAUGCUUCUCCCUGCUUAUCCGUACUUUUUCAUUUGCUUUAGGAGAGAGCACUUAUUCAAUAACUUCCCGUCUUCAUUUUCCUAGACAACAUUAAAUUCUUAAGUGCUUUUAUUGAUGCCUUUAAGUGUUGCCAACCCUCUAGUGGAACUGCAAAACCUAUUGGGAUAGCACAGUUAUAAAGAAUUAGAUACUAGGUAUAGAAAAAUCACUGUGCAUAUACUGUAUAUGUUAUAUAAUAGUAUCAUAUAUGGGGAAGAACUUUAAACUUCUUGAAGAAAAAAGCAUUUCCAAAUCAUGUAUCCUAGAAAAAGCUUAACAAGGUUUAGGACACCAGAAGGGACCUGGAAUUUUAAAGACGUUAUUCUUUAUGCAUAACACUUGGCAUUCUUUUCUUAGGAAAAGAAAGGAGCUUAGGCUUUCUUUUCAAGAAAGCCAAGUGUCAUGUUAUACAUAAAGAAUAACAUUUAGCAUUAGGCAUUGAAGGUAUUUCAAGAUUGUGCAUGUCUAGGACAGUAUACACAUUUUUUUCCCCAUGAAAAUACCAAAGACCUUCAUUUUUUUGAGAUUUCUCCACUUAAAAAAUUUGUUCCUAGGUUUUCUCAAAAGAUUUCCUAGAAACCACAGAGGUUUAUAGCCAAUAUAAACCCAUUUGCAGCUUUUUGUGCUGUAAUGAAAUUUCAAAAUUUGUCACGUGCUCUGACAUUUCCCAUCCUCACUCUGUCUGUCCCUCUCACUGUGUGCCUUUGAGUGAUAGCACUGCAUGUACUUUGUGAUGUGUGCUGCCUUUAGCUACAGUCUGGUAGUCACAGUUACUCUAACCCUUUAGAAUGCCUGGGGCUCAGUGUUACUUGAAUGCCGUCUCCAUGGCACUUUCCGCUCAUAUUUCCCAUUUAUGUCAACCCCUUUUGUUGCCUUACACGUACUAUUUGUUCCUGUCUUUCUGCCUCCAGCUUGUAUUCCACACCUUACUUUUUCCCUUACCUGCUUCUUCAGCCAUUUUACUUUAAUUAUCUCAGGAUGUCUCAGCAUGUCUUCCCAAAGACAUGCCAACUAGACUGACUUCAUUCUUUUUGUUCUUCCUUCUAAAGGUUGAACUAGGGUGAUCCGUUUUUAAUGUAAUGAUACUAAAGGGGUGUAGGAGCAACUUGAGUAUAAGAAAAGAAUAGAUAAUAGGAAAAUUAUAAUAAAACCAAAAUAUUUAAUAAACAUAAUAAUGCAUGUCUUAUUCUAAAGAAGAGUUCAAUAACAUACUCUAAUAUGACACUGGCAAAAUUCUAACGAAUAUUUGUUCAUUAAGAAGAAAGUGUAUAUGAUGAUGGGACUUCCUGGGAAGUUGAAGAUAGUAUUGUUGGGAUUGGCUGGUGGAUGCAUAAACACCAGGUAGUAAAGAAAGCAUGUCAAUAGAAGUAUCAGAUGCCCAUUCAUACUGUAAAUACUGUGUGUAAAACUGUUACAAGUGACAGUUGUAUGUAAAUUUUAAAUGCACUGAUAAAUAUUGUCAUAUACAUAAUAAUUUAAAAUUAUAAUUAGAUAUCCCUUGCCUUCCUUAAACGCUUCUCUUCUUUUUCCCCUCCUUUUCAACUUUUUCCCUUGCCCCUUUUUUCCCCACCCCUUAAACUGAUGUUUCUCAAAGCAUGGCCCUAAACUACCUAUAUCAGAAUCACCUAGAAGUUUUUGAAAAGUGUAUAAUCCCCUAGCCUCAUCCCAGAUUUAUUGAAUGACAAUCCUUGUGGAUGUUAAACAUCCAAUAUUUUUAGCAUUGAUGAUUCUUAAAUAGAUAAAAGUUUGAGGAUCACUGCUAAAAAGUACCCGUUAACACUGAAUUCUGUCCUCAUCCUCUCAAAGUUGCCUUGGCGAAUCAAUUCCCUUCUGCAGUUGUAGCUACUACUUCUGAGUAGAAGAUUCCAAACUUCUCUUAUAUUCUGACCUCUUUCCCACACUUCAUUUCCACAAUUCCAACUGUUUUCAUCAGUAGGUCCAUCAGGUGUUGUAAGAGAGUAGUCUUCACUAUUAAAAUAAGUAGUCUUCACUAUUAAAACCCUCCAAAUGUUUAGUAAAGAAUUAUGAGAGCAGUAUCUUUAGGUAGAGAGGAUGGCAGAGUAAUACUAACUGCAAUGUCUGUGAGUUUCACUUUCCAAGUUUUUUUUUUCUUGCCAAAGCUGCAUCCUAGCCACACCAUUUAAAUCUCAGAAACAGCAUACUCUAAACUGGUUAAAAGUAUAAGCUUAAGUAUUUGCUUUGCCACUUACUAGCAGUAGAAUUUGGGAGCAAGCUAUUUUAUUUCUCUUAGCCUAAGUUUUCUCAUCUGUAAAGUAGGAACAAAAACAGUAAUAAUAAUUAGGGUUUUGAUUGUGGAGAUUAGAUAUGUAAUACGUUUUAAGCAUUUAGUAUAGGACCUAGCAAUUAGUAAGUGAUUGAUUAAUCUUAGCUGUUACUUGCAAUAAAAGCAAGUAACCUCCUAUCUUAGUAUAGCUGAGAUAGAUUUUAAUUGUCCUAGCUGUGUGUGGUGGUGCACAGCUGUAGUCACAGCUACUUGGGAGGCUGAGGUGGUAGAAUCGCCUGAGCCCAGGAGUUCAAGGCCAGCCUGAGCAAGAUAGUGAGACCCUGUCUCUUAAAAUAAUUUUUUUAAUUUUUAAUUUUCCAAAAGAAAUUUAAUAAAUAAUAAAGGAAUAUGAGGAAAGGUAAUAUGAGAAACAUAAAAAGUCAAACUUUUAAAGUAUAGGUUUCUAAUCCUAGAGUACUUUACUUAUAUCUAAUAAAACCUAUCUAAGUACUAGGCCAAAGAAAAUUCCUAAGUAGUCCCUAGGCUAUUUCCCCUUCUGUUAUGUGUUUCCAUCUUUCCUGAGAAGGAGAUCCAGUCAGAUAUCAUACGGUUAUAAAAAAGAGUUUCAUGGCCUUCAAGGUGUAGAAGGAAAAUGCACUUCUCAACAUUCCCUUCUGUAGGUCCCUAUCACCACAAAAGUCAGGGUCACCAGGAUCCUCUCUCAUUUCACUGAAGAUUAAAACACAGUUCAUAAACAGAGUCAAGAAACUAGUAUGUCAUUAAUCCCCUCACUGAAAUAAAUACUUUGAACUCUAUAUGUCUGAAACUGAAAUCAUGAUAUCUUUCCCUCGCACAAACAACCUGCAAAAGAGCCUGCCAUUAUUCUACUCUGUCAACUUUGAAAUCUCUAAAUCAUUCUUGACCCCUCUCUUAACUUGUUACACUUUGUUCUUUACUCUUCAUCUUCAUUGCCAUGACUCAGAUUUGGGCCCUCAUGACCUAAAUUGUUAUCACAGACCCAUAACUAGUUGCUGAACUAUUCUAGAAUGAAUGUUUUACCGAUUUUCUUAAAAUACACCUGAGAUCAGUUCAGUCCCCUGCUCCAAAACCUUUAGCAACUUUCCAUUACCUGUCAAAUGAUUGUUCAAUUCUUUAACCAGUAUUUUAUAAUUUUUGUUCUCUGAACUCAGCCUCUUUGGUUCAGUCUUAGCUCUCUCUGUUCUCCUAAAAAUACUCAGGUUGUAGUCAAAUCCCAUAUUUUCUUGUCACGUCACUUUGAUGGACUGUUCCCUCUUACUGAAAAGUCUUGCCACCAACUCUUUGCCUACCAAAUCUGUUUUUCCAGGACAACUUAAAUGCCACUCUUUACUGCUUACCUCAACUAACCAUGACCUAUCUUCUGAACCCUCAUAACAGUGUCUGUACCUCUUUGGCACUUAUUACUGAUUGUUAUUGGUGUAUUACUACUGAACUGUAUUCUCCUUAGGGGCAGGAAAAGUAUCUUUUAAAAAACACUGUACCUAGACAGUCAUUAGCAGAGCCUUUGAUAUAUAUGUUCAACAAACUUUUUAUUAAGUUAUUGAGGUUACUACAUUUCUACUGUAAUCAUGAUAAUAUAAAAAUUAUAAUUUAAAACACAGUUAUAAAAUUAAUAAUAUUCACUUUGAUCACUUUCCAAUGCUUUCUAUAUGGAAAUAUAUGAGUUAUAUAUGAGUUAGGAAUGCUUAUUUGAAAUUAAGUUCCUGUUUAUCAUAAAAAGAUUUUUGUUCACGAUUACCAUGAAAUGGACUUAUCCUAAUUGUGUCUGUAGUUUGCAAAGGCCCAGUUUGUCUUCAUUGCUUUGAGUAAAAUAACUAGCUUUUCUAUUGUAUAUGCAGAAAUAUGGUCAACUUGAAGAAUAUCUCAAUUUUGCGGAUUACUUUCAAGAAGAGAAGUUUGAGUUGUAACACAUUUCCAUCAGAGAAGAUUUUUUAAAUUCCUGUAAAUGUGAAGAUCAUGAUUCUUGUUUUUCUGUAUCAUGUGACAUGUUUGUACAUUUUAUCUAUAUCUUCAUGGCAAAAUAUUUUGUUUAAAACAUGAUUAUCUUAAUUCCUGUGAAGUGGCACUCUACACUCUAAUUAAACUUUUAUCUGAUGUACAUAAAAGCAUUAUCUUAAUUUUUAAGUCUGUAAAUAUAUUUUAAAGUUAUAUAAUAAUGGCUUUAUAACAGAUGACUGUCAAGUGAAUGAGCUGUUGAUAUCCUGUCAGUUUAGUCAAAAUAUAUUGUAUCUUAAAAAUGUAUUUAGACUAACGUCUACAUGUAUUUUUACGGAAUUCCUGUCCAGAUCUGUUUAUUCUUUUACAGUAUUAAAUGAUUUUCACUAAUAUAUUUUUUACUGCUAUCAUCUAAAUCAGUGGGCCAUGGAAGAAACCUCAUAUAUCAUUCAGUUCAAUCCCAUUGCUUCAGAAUCAGAUCAUAGCAUAUCUAUUCUAAGUAGAGGAAUGCUUUUUUCCUUUUCUUGAAAGUUUCUCUUUCAAAUAGAUUUCAGGCCUCUAGAGUCUUUCAACCCUCACAUUCAGGAAUAAUUUUAUGUAAAUUUUCAUGCUUUAUAAUGUUCUUACUUUUUUCUAUUCAAUUUUGUCUAUAUAUUGAUGAUUAAGAUGUAUUUUAUUUAUUUUUAUCCAUAGCUUUUUCCAUAUAAGUAUGUAUCUUAGGGUCAGAACUGCUGAAAGAGACAAACUCAGCCAAAAACACUUGGAAAGCAUAUUUUGGUAUCUGCAUUGCUUUGCAUAUCUAAAUUUUCCCAUAAAGUAAUAAAGUAAAAUGGUUGCAGAGUGAA